GCAGUGUCAACGAGCCCCCGAACGGUUCCGCCUCAUUCCCUCUCUGUGUGCCUCGCAAGUCUCUGCUUAGUAAACCGUCACAGCUUCGGCGCGCGAGAGUGGCGUUGGCACGUCCAAACCCCGGGGUCCUCGGCCAGGCCAGGGGGGCGGGCGUGCGGCGGGGCCGGGCCGGGCCGGGCGCGCCCAGCGGGCUCCGGGCACACGCCCCUCACCUGGGCGAGGCCCGGUGCGCAGGCGCUCAGCGCGGGGGCAGCGGCCGGGCGCUUAAGCCCGGCGCGGGCAAGAGUUGGACAGUUCAGGGGCCGCGCCGGGCCGAGCUGUCGCCCGCGCCACCUCCACCGCCGCCGCUGCUACCGCCACCGCCACCGCCUGGGCUGCAGCAGAUCGCGGGAGAACGUCUGCGCGAAGCCCCGGUGCAGCCCUGGCGGGACCGCAGCAACCACCGGAGCGUGAGCAACAGCUUCCCGGCUGGAGGAGCCACUGCCCCACGCGCCCGCGGCCCGCGCGCCGAGAUGUUCUACAUUUCAACUCCAUCAAAUAUUAAAUUGAUGUUUAUGGGCUAACCUGGAAACCGAAAAACAGUUUGUUUCACUACAAGAAUAAGAAAAUAUGUCCAAAUUCCUGUCAGCUGACUUAUAAAGGGACUUUUAGAACACAACCCAAUGCAUGAGGUACUCCUUAAGCCCUGACAACCAUCUUGAAGAUGGAAUCAUGAAUAUGGCAAAUUUUCUACGGGGCUUUGAAGAAAAGGGGAUAAAGAACGACAGGCCUGAGGACCAGUUGAGCAAAGAGAAAAAGAAAAUUCUUUUCUCCUUCUGUGAGGUGUGCAACAUCCAGCUGAACUCUGCAGCCCAGGCUCAGGUGCAUUCCAACGGCAAAUCCCACCGCAAACGAGUGAAGCAGCUGAGUGAUGGGCAGCCCCCACCACCCGCCCAGGCCAGCCCCAGCAGCAACAGCAGCACAGAUAAUCAGGGCUGGAGCCAAGUCUCGGUAGCGCUGUGCAUUAUCCUGGUCACAUACUGGAAGUUUUGUUUAUCCAACUUGGUUGCUCUUGAAGCUGGUGAGAGCCCUGCCAGGAUGUGGAGUGGACUUCCUAGCAGAGGCAGUACAUGCCACACUACUACCCUUCCUGCUCUUGUGCGCACACCUACCCUGAUGAUGCAGCCUUCACUGGAUAUCAAACCAUUUAUGUCUUUUCCAGUGGACAGUAGUUCUGCUGUUGGGCUCUUUCCAAAUUUUAACACAAUGGAUCCUGUGCAAAAAGCGGUUAUUAACCAUACAUUUGGAGUAUCCAUUCCCCCAAAGAAGAAACAAGUUAUUUCUUGUAAUGUCUGUCAGCUUCGCUUUAACUCAGAUAGCCAGGCCGAGGCCCACUACAAAGGAAGUAAACAUGCCAAGAAGGUCAAAGCACUAGACGCAACGAAAAAUAAACCCAAAAUGGUUCCUUCCAAGGACAGCGCAAAGGCUAAUCCCAGCUGCUCCAUCACUCCAAUCACAGGCAACAACUCUGACAAAUCAGAAGAUAAAGGGAAGUUAAAAGCCAGCAGUUCCAGUCAGCCAUCAAGCUCUGAAAGUGGCUCAUUUCUCCUCAAAUCUGGCACAACACCCCUGCCACCUGGAGCAGCCACUUCUCCCUCCAAGAGCACAAAUGGAGCUCCCGGUACUGUUGUUGAAUCAGAAGAAGAAAAAGCCAAAAAAUUACUUUAUUGUUCACUAUGCAAAGUGGCUGUGAACUCCCUGUCACAGCUAGAGGCACACAACACAGGAUCUAAACACAAGACCAUGGUUGAAGCUCGUAAUGGGGCUGGUCCAAUUAAAUCCUAUCCUAGACCUGGAUCAAGAUUAAAGAUGCAGAAUGGCAGUAAGGGGUCAGGACUACAGAACAAGACAUUUCAUUGUGAAAUCUGUGAUGUUCAUGUUAAUUCAGAAAUUCAACUCAAACAGCACAUUUCUAGCCGAAGGCAUAAAGAUCGAGUUGCAGGGAAACCACUGAAGCCAAAAUACAGCCCUUACAACAAACUCCAGCGGAGCCCGAGUAUUCUAGCAGCAAAACUUGCAUUCCAGAAAGAUAUGAUGAAGCCUUUGGCCCCAGCCUUCCUGUCCUCACCUCUCGCAGCGGCGGCAGCCGUGUCCUCAGCGCUGUCACUCCCACCCCGGCCCUCUGCCUCGCUCUUCCAGGCUCCAGCCAUUCCUCCAGCUCUUCUGAGGCCUGGGCAUGGGCCCAUCCGCGCCACUCCUGCCUCCAUCCUCUUUGCUCCGUACUAACGUCUGCAAACCCCAAGACGUUUGAGGCCAGUAGGAAGUUGAGAAAGAAAGCCACAAGGAUUCAGCAAUUUAAGCAGUUUGUGUUGCAGUACCCCCCAUUCACCCACAAAAUGCAGCCCACCACCCAGUCCCCCAAUUCCAGAGAGAAACACAUCACUAGAUUGACGAGGGCUUUUAGAGACUGCUCCUAUAAUUGAGGAAUCAGCAGCAUAGGCUUUAUCUCCCUACUUCCUCCCCCACCCUACCGCGUUCAAUUUGUGUAUCUCAGAUAUUUGAUUUCUUGAGCAUGUAUUGGUCAGAAAGAAAAAGAAAGAAAACCAUUCUCUAUUUUUCCAUGGGUAUGAUCUGGCUUAAAACAAUAUGGAAUAUUUUCCUGACAGACUUGAAAACUAGGAUCUUCCUCAGAUGUCUGUAAAUAACUCUGGUAUCCAACUGGGUGUAUUCUAGUGUGGAACAAAAAACAGUGAACACAAGUGCUUACUUGUGGAUACUAUCUUACCAACGGAUCACAAAGUUCUCUUUUUGGUGUACUGUUGUUGACAGGGAUUGUGUACUGUUUCGACCCAAGUACUGCUGUAUCCUGUGUAGUACUAGAUCUGUAUCUCUUGUCUGAAUUAAACAUUUUUAGUUGCUGUGUAAAUGUUAGGAAGCAAAGUAGCUUUGAAUUUUCUCUGUAAGAGAAUAAAAGAUAAAAUAAUGUAUUUUCUUUAUUUCACAUUUUAUUUGGAGAUAUUUAAAUGAAAUAGAAAGCCAUAUAACAUAGCUAUAAUUACUACCUGUUUGCUAUUUUUGUUUAACUUAUUUUGUAGCUUCCUCACUGGUUUGUGUUGCUAAGCAAACGUAUACAAACAGAAAAAGAGCUUCCUAAAUUGCACAUUUUUGCACCUCUUGUGCAUUCUGCAAGAAGACAAUGAAUCCAUGUAUUUCUAUAUAAGUAUCUUCUUCAUUUUUAACCUGUUUUCAUUUGUAAUGAUGCUACAUAAUUUUGUGGCUCCCUAAUGCAAUAAUGUACAGAAGAUAAAAAAAUUUAUAAUUGAACAAUUUGUCUUUCUGUUCGCUGAAUAUAUUGCAGGUCAUGCUCCCAUGCCCCCCUUUCUAAGCCGAUAUCAACAAGACUGGAAUGUUUGUGAUAUCAGGGGCAAGAGUUAUCAUAGAACAACAAAAUAGAGUGGACUCUUUUAGAGCAUCUAUAUCUGCAACCUGUAAAUGGUAAAAUGUCUGUGUAUUUUUUUAAAUGUACCUUUUCAAUAAAAGUACAAAAAAUAAAA